AGGGUGUGGGGUGGCUGGGGAUGGCGUGAGGUCCAGGGAACAGGAGGGGCUCUCGUGCACCAGCGUGGGUGGAGAAAUCAAACAGGAUGAAGCCUCGACAGAAAGAACAGGACACGAGACUGAGGAAGCUCCGAGAGAGCAGCGAGGGAGACCAGUGGCUGGAAAAUGAGAAAACAAAGCCACUGAGGCCCCAGCAGCAGCCCCAGUGCCAACCAGCAGGGGGCACAGGACAGAGAAGAGGAAGCGGCAGCAGCCCCAGCGCCGACCAGCAGGGGGCACAGGACAGAGAAGAGGAAGCGGCAGCAGCCCCAGCGCCGACCAGCAGGGGGCACAGGACAGAGAAGAGGAAGCCGCAGCAGCCCCAGCGCCGACCAGCAGGGGGCACAGGACAGAGAAGAGGAAGCCGCAGCAGCUCCAGCGCCGACCAGCAGGGGGCACAGGACAGAGAAGAGGAAGCGGCUGCAGCCCCAGCGCCGACCAGCAGCGGGCACAGGACAGAGAAGAGGAAGCCGCAGCAGCCCCAGUGCCGACCAGCAGCGGGCACAGGACAGAGAAGAGGAAGCGGCUGCAGCCCCAGCGCCGACCAGCAGCGGGCACAGGACAGAGAAGAGGAAGCCACAGCAGCCCCAGUGCCGACCAGCAGCGGGCACAGGACAGAGAAGAGGAAGCGGCUGCAGCUCCAGUGCCAACCAGCAGGGGGCACAGGACAGAGAAGAGGAAGCCGCAGCAGCCCCAGCCGCCAACCAGCAGGGGGCACAGGACAGAGAAGAGGAAGCCGCAGCAGCCCCAGCGCCGACCAGCAGCGGGCACAGGACAGAGAAGAGGAAGCGGCUGCAGCCCCAGCGCCGACCAGCAGGGGGCACAGGACAGAGAAGAGGAAGCCGCAGCAGCCCCAGCGCCGACCAGCAGGGGGCACAGGACAGAGAAGAGGAAGCGGCUACAGCCCCAGCGCCGACCAGCAGGGGGCACAGGACAGAGAAGAGGAAGCCGCAGCAGCCCCAGCGCCGACCAGCAGCGGGCACAGGACAGAGAAGAGGAAGCGGCUGCAGCUCCAGUGCCAACCAGCAGGGGGCACAGGACAGAGAAGAGGAAGCGGCUGCAGCUCCAGUGCCAACCAGCAGGGGGCACAGGACAGAGAAGAGGAAGCGGCAGCAGCCCCAGUGCCGACCAGCAGCGGGCACAGGACAGAGAAGAGGAAGCCGCAGCAGCCCCAGCGCCGACCAGCAGCGGGCACAGGACAGAGAAGAGGAAGCGGCAGCAGCCCCAGCGCCGACCAGCAGCGGGCACAGGACAGAGAAGAGGAAGUGAGGAAAUGGAAGAAGAGGGUUGACCUGAGCUGAAGGACAUGAACUUCCACGUGAAAUAGCCCCAGGGCCGGGCACAGUGGCGCACGCCUGUAAUCCCAGCACUUUGGGAGUCUGAGGCAGGAGGAUUCCUUGA